AUGCCCCAACUAAAUACUACCGUAUGGCCCACCAUAAUUACCCCCAUACUCCUUACACUAUUCCUCAUCACCCAACUAAAAAUAUUAAACACAAACUACCACCUACCUCCCUCACCAAAGCCCAUAAAAAUAAAAAAUUAUAACAAACCCUGAGAACCAAAAUGAACGAAAAUCUGUUCGCUUCAUUCAUUGCCCCCACAAUCCUAG